UGGAAGUCAGGUCCCAUCUUCGUACUUGGCUUCCACCUCUGAAAAACAAUUUAUGAUUUCUAUGUUCCCUUCUAAGCUCUAAAAUUCUGAUUGGCUUCUCAGUACUUAACUGUUUAAGGGUAAUAUGUGUGAAGUUAACUGACACAAAGAUAUUACCGAUGGCUGAGCCUAAGUCCUGACAAACUGGGAUGUGUAAUCUUAAGUUUGUAUGGACGGAAAAAUUGUCUAAGUGCAUACUGCAAGUGAAGCACUGGGCUGGAUAUUAUAGUGCAAUCAAAGAUGAAUGUCGUCAAUGCUUUCCUCCAGAGGCUGAAAGCUAGCCAGAGAUAAGAUGUAUGUAUGACUAGCUUAUGUGCAAGGUUCAUAGCGGUGGUAUUAUUAAGCCUCAACACUGGGUGUUAUCUUUAAAACGAACUUGGUCAGCCUGCCCUAGUUAAAAAUUCUUUACCAGCUCCCCAUUACUAACAGAAUAUAACCUAAGCUCUUAGCAUCUAGAAACCUUCCUGAACUCAAGCCUGUUUGUCUCAUCUCAUCUGCAGAAUCACCUUUGCUCCCCAGACAUCUCUACUCCUCCACCCAAUUUUUUUUACUUUGUGCCUUCACGUGUAAUGAUAAAGUCCUUCAGUUGGAAUGCUAGCUUGUCUUGUUCUUCUUUCUGUCUACUGCAUGUCCCAAGCCAUACUUUUUCCCUUCUGAACCACAACCUCUCACACCUGGCCAACUCCUGUUUCCCCUUUGUGAGUCAUCCUUGGGUGCUAGAGUCCCCCACAACCUUUCCUGGAUUUCCCCUGGGUAGCCCCAGGAAGUCCUUUUCUACCUUGUCAUGGAAGCUUACACUCCACCAUUCUGCUGCUUAUGAUACACUAUAUAAUUGUGUUUGCAUGUUUAUCUCCCUACUUGACAGUAACAUCCAUGGGAACAGGGCUUUGUCUUUUCACUUGUGUGUCCCCAGCACACAGUCCAGUGACUGGGACUGCAAAUACUGUUGUGUUUGUAGAAGGCCUGAAAAUGUUUGGAAAAGUCACCUAAAACACAGGAGAGAGAUCAGAGUCAAAGCCGGGGAACAAGUAGUGAGAAUGUGGAGUGAUGAGAUUGGGGAUGGAGAGGGCCAGUGGUGAGGAGGGGGGCGGUUGAGGCUUGGAAGCUUUACUUUAGGGCACUGGGAGGGAGAAGUCUGCAAAAGAGCACAACUGGGGAAGAAGAAAGUUUAGCCAGGAUGAGGCAGUCAUCAUGGCGCUCACAGGUGGGGAGAGAGUCAUUGUAAGAAAAGGCUAUUGAAUCGGUUGUUAGGUGGUGAUUGGUGACCUUUGAAAGGGCAGUUUCAAGGAAGUCUUUAGAUUAAGAAGCCAGAUUUCCUGAGAUAAGAAGGAUUUUUAUAAGCAGAAAAACAAUAAAAGUAAUUGUUUUAAAGAAAUAAAGGUGAGUGAAUGAUGCCAACAGAACAGAGAGGGAAGGGAUAGUAUUUUGAGGUGGUGGCACGGUACAGCUGAUAUUAUUACAUGUUUUAAAAACUAGAGCUUAUGAAAACAGGGCCGUAGACAAAAGGAGUCAGCAGGAGGGGAAAGGAUUACAGAUAUGGAAAGAGAAUGGGAGGAUGUUCUCUGAAGAAGCAGGAAGGAGGCAGUCAACUCAGGGCAAAGCGGAGGGUCGGAGGUUGCGGCCUCUGUCUCCUAGAGGGAAUUGGGGAAGCGUGUUAUGAGACGGAGCCAGAGAUCGAGGCUGUUCAUUACAUGGUGUGGGAGCCUUGCUUGCAAUGUGGCCCCCGCCAUAUUGUUAGUUCUUUGGUGAAAAGGAUGACUUUAUUUGGUGCUCUCUCGCUCAGGUCUUGUGAAUUUAAUUAGGUUGACUUUUCAAAGACAAAUGAUAUUAUUAAAGGCUUAAAAAAAAUAUGUGUGGUAUUUCAUUUGGCUCUAUUGGAAUUUUUGUCCUGAGGGAAAGUUGCCCAGCCGGGUGAAACCACGGAUUAAAUGCCCUAUUGAGAAAAAGAAAAGAGCAGACAAAAAUAUGGGAUUAACAGAAUGGGAAUUAUAUACAAAAAGGGGCUAUUUAACUUCUCCUAUUGAAUUUGAUGGCACGGAAUUUUCUAUAAUACUAAGUACUACUCUGGGUACAGUAACUCCAAAAGAAGUGCUUUCCUUGGUGUCCUUAACUCGGGAGAGGGAAGUUGGAUGCAAGAGCAAAGGAAAAAUGAACAAUCAUUGCUUUUUCAGAUAGUUAAAGAGACGUGUUGCCCCCACCCCCAUACCUUUUUUUUUUUUUUUUUUUUUAACGGUAAGCAACACAGAAAAGAUAGAAUGGCAAAGACAGUCAUUUAAAUGAUCCAGGUCUUAACAAAGCACUGCGGAUUGUUUAAACAAAAGGCUUUUUGUUUUGUUUUUGUGUCUGUAGCCAGUCUGCUGUUUCAGCAAUUCUAUUUUAACUCCCGAUAAAGUAAGUAACUUGAGUGGCCUCUAUAUUUCACUCAGGGCAGCAUAAAAACGAUACAUUGAAGGUACUGUUGGUAAGGUUUGUUAUCAUUCACGAUACAACCGAAGUCUCCCGUGUUGGCUUAGAAUCUUUGCAGGCGAUUUGAUCUUGAGUAACCUUGGUGAUGCUCCUCUGCUGCCAAUGAUACGGCUUUUUAAUUCUAAAGUGAAAUGAGAUCGCCUCCAAUUUGGCUGCUCUCUCUGGUGGUGCUCAACUAGGACUUGCAGACUCUCAGCACACUCACAUUAAUCAUGGCAUCAGAAAGCUCUCACCUUAAUUUAAAUCAGAUUUAGUUCUUCAAGGCUUCUUAAAUUAAUCUGGGCAUGUGACAAGAAGAAAUGUUAAAAGCUGGUUUUCUGCAAUGGCAAAUGACAUUUUAAUAAUAAUUCUUGCCAUGGUGUGCAAUGAAAAACAAAGCUAACAGACAGUUUAUCCAGUGGCUCAACUUUUAAUGUUUAACUCCUUAAGGUUUUUUGUUGUUGUUUGUCUGUUUUGUUUUGUUUUGGGAGGUUUUAAUUUCACUCUAAUAGGAAUUAAUCACAGAGCAAGAAUAUUAAUCAAAAUGGCCGUUUAUUUUUAACCCUUCUACAUAAAAUGAGAUUGUCUAUGGUGUUUAAUGUCAGUGACAGAGAUAUUGGUCCCAAGACAUGGGGGAAAACCAGUCUUUCUAAAAUGUGUUAAUGCAUUGUUAACAAAUUCAUUUCCAGUUUGACUGUUGAGCCGAUGACCACAAUUAGUAGUGUAUUUUCCCUCUGUGGUUCUUCCCAACCUGGUCAUUUUAUUUUGCUAAAUAUACAAUGUAAAUUGUAUAUUUACAUUGUAAAUGAGAAGUCAUUUGGAAUUGUGUUAUUAUAAAAUAAUUUUUAGGCAGUCUGCUUAUCAUUCCUUUUUUUUACCCCCUCCCCUGGCAAAGAAACCUGUCCAUUUCAAAGGUAGCAUUCUGUCACCACCUCCUCUCUUACAUCUUACUCCCCGCCUACACUUGCCUGCAAGCUUUUUCUGAAAAUGCAGCUUUCCUGUGGCAUCUGUUCUGUCUGACUAGAAAGCUUUGGGGAGUUGCCCAUGAUGCAGUUAGCUUUUUAAUCCUAGAUUGGUCAGUUUCCCUGAAAUUCUACUGAGACAAAAUUUCCUUGGAUAGAUAACCAUGAUGGUGCACCAGACAUCAUCUUCCUUAUUCAUUCUGUUCCACCUACUCUCCUCUCAUCCUCUUAUUACUCAAAUAUGUGAGUUGUGGAUGGGAGAAGAGGCCCAUUUAAUGGGAGGUCAGGUCAUAUGCCUUGGGUUAAUGAAGGUGGAAAAUGUGGCUGAGGAUAAAAUCUACCUGGGUGACCAAUGGGGCCAUCACCUUUGUCAUAUAGUUACAGUACCCCUUCAAGCACGCUACUGUCCAACAAAUACAGAUCAUUCAUUCAUUUAAGGAACUCACCGAGCACCAGCCAGCCACCCACAUUGAGCCAUAUCAUGUAGGGCUUAGAAACCAUUAGGAGGAUUUUGGCUUUUACAUUCAGGGCGUGGAGAGAUUUGAACUUAGAAGUGACAUAAUCUGACUCAUUAGUUUGAAAUGGAUCCAUCUGAUUGUGUGUUGAAAGUUCACAGUAAAGGAGACAGGGGUGUCAAUGUAGGAGACCAGGUGGAGGUCACCAUCAGGUGAGAGAUGGUGGAGGCCUGAUCAGGAAGUUUUCCCUGCAGUUGCAGCUGGAGUGGAAUGUUAAAAUAAAUGUAAGAACCCUCCAAGCAUUUUAAGGAAAUCUUGACAUGUAAGACACAUUUCUACAGUAGCAAAGCUAAAGCUUUUCCUGAAACAAAAUGGCAUUCUUUAGGGACUAAAAGUAGAUACCAGAUAUAGCAUUCCCCCACCAUUGAUCUGUACCAUAUCAGCUAAAUUCUUUAUCCUAUGUUCCCUUUUAAGUUAUUCGCUUGGCGAGUGUGGAUCAUUUGUGACAUAAUAAAAAGAACAGACCAACCCUCUUUUCCUUUGGGCAUUUUAUCAUUUGUCAUGUGGAAUAUGUAGGAAGCAAAAUUCUAUUGCCCUCUUUGGGAUCCCCACCGAACACCUCCUCUGAGUAGAGAAGACUUCUCCUCUUUCACUUUUACCUCCACCCUAAAUGGAUAUCAUGUUGAUCCCUUUAAUUUUAUUUCUACUUCUCUUUAGGUAUUUGCCUUACUCUGAAACAGUUUUCUCACGGUGUGGCUCACAGGACAGCUGCAUCAGCAUUGAUUGAGGACUUGCUAGGAAUCCAAGUUGUCAGGCUCCAUCCCAGACCUACUGAAUCAGAUAUGGGAGUGGACUCAGCAGUAUUUUUAUAACAAGCCCUCCAGGGGAUUCUGAUGUACCUUAAUUUGGGAUGCCACUGCUCUGUACAUUGGCCUGUGAAUUUGUUUAAUCAGGCAGCUAAACUGUAAGCACCUUGAAGGCGGGAAUGUAACCCUUUAGUCCCACUACCCUUUACAAGCUACAAGUUAGGAUUCCAAGACACAGCUACCCAGUUUCAGAGUUGGUGCUCUUGACUGCUGCUGCUCUUCUCUCUCGUUGGUGGCAAAGGUGACUUGAGAAACUGGUGUUGAUGCCUCUGUGUAUUCAUUCUGUGUUUUCUCCAAGCUAGCUCUGCCUUGACUGUCUGGAAGAAGAGUAUUCAGAGGUUUAGAAAAAAAUGGCUGGCCAAAGCACAGGUCAGGAGAAUCACUGAACCUGGAGGUUGGAAAGAAAACAUAAUUGUCACCAGCUUGACUUUCUCUUUUCCAACUUUCUGGUGGUAUAAGUCUAGAUAACUUUCAUCCUCCUUUUUUUUUUUUUUUUUUUUUGAGACGGAGUCUCGCUCUGUCACCCAGGCUGGAGUGCAGUGGUGCCAUCUCAGCUCACUGCAACCUCCGCCUCCCGGGUUCAAGCAAUUCUCCUGCCUCAGCCUCCUGAGUAGCUGGGACUACAGGCACCCGCCACCACGCCCAGCUAAUUUUUGUAUUUUUAAUAGAGAUGGAGUGUCACCAUGUUGAACAGGCUGGUCUUGAACUCCUGACCUUGUGAUCCGCCCGCCUUGGCCUCCCAAAUGUUGGGAUUACAGGCGUGAGCCACCACGCCCGGCUUCAUCUUCUUUUUUUAAGGCAAAGUAAGACUUAGUCCCUUCAGGAAAUUUCCCUUUUCCCUGACACCAGGGUGAUAGUUGGCAUACUUUCAUAUUGGCCCUCUCUUUCUUGCUUCACCUGCAGCUAAGCACAUUGUACUCUAUUACCUGGAAUGUUUUGUCUUUAUAGAUUCCAUUAAGAGAUAAAAUAUUUACUUUUAGAACUUUUAGAAAGUCUUGGGCUUACUCGUUAAAGACAUGUAUUUUCUCUUUUUUAUGUUUUAUGUUACUUUGAAUGCUAAGUGUCACUGAAGUGAUAAUUGGUGAAGAAGUGGUCUUAUGGGCUCAAAUUUGCAUUUAUUAGGAGGCAAAUUUGAGUUUAAUACUUGAAAUAUAAAAGCAUGCUUUUAUGCUGUUAUACAUAUUCCUGUAUAGCUACAUAAAACAGCUCUUGCUCUAAAAAGAGGGGAAGGGAGAAAAGAAUAAAUCAUUAGUCUAAUAAUAAACCAAAAGGGCCUAUUUAUUUGAAACUUAUUUAAAACUACUAUAAAUUAUAAAGGAAAAUAUUCAUUGAAAAGAUCUGUAUUAAAUACACAGUGUCUUUGAGAUUUAAAACAGCUUUUCACCUCUUUGAUAUGCUACACACAACUGAGUGACUUAAAUGUUUGAACAUCUAUUGUCUUUUAAUUAUGUUCUAGUUUGUUUAUUGUUGAAGACAAUUUAAAUAAAUUGAAGUUCAACUGCUUUGAAGAAUUUAUGGAAAAUCUAAACAUAUUUUUGGAAAAUUCAUCGUGCAUGAGUGACAAGGGAGAAUCCUAACUAUAUCAGUAUGAUUUCUUUCUCUUUUCCAGUAUUGCCAAGCCCAACAAAUUUAUGAAGGGGUAGGUAAAUAAAUCCCUUCUAUUUUAAAUGCACUUUGGUUUGGUUUUUCAUUAAGAAAAUAAGUUCUCUAAUAUUCACAAUACAUGAUAUUUAGGUGCAGUCAGUUUUUCCUGUGUAUUUAUUUGAAAGCUCAAACUAGAUUAUUUAGCUAUACAAUACUUCAUUCAGCUAUUGGGCUGGAAUUCAUUUUCUUCUAAACAUGAAUGUUUAUAGUCUUAUGUAUUCUCAGUCCUUCUGGACUAAGAUGAAGUUUUGUGAUAGAACUGGCCUUUUACCCUGUUAUUAAUAAUCUGGUAGAUUAUUAACUGAGAUAGAAGUUUAAAAACUUCGAUCUACCAGAAACUUUAUACCUGGGCUUCAGAAUCUGUAAGACUGAUACAAUAACUGCUUUCCUUCAAUUCUCAGAGAAUUAUUGUAAACACAAAUCAGGUAAUGAUAACAAGAGGCUUUCAGUUUUAAAAAGUGUCAGUAGUAUUAGCUUUAAAAAUCAGUCAUCCGAAAAAAGAUUUUUUAGACUCUAGAUCAUCAUAGGACUUUCUCACUGAAGCAGUACAUCAUGACUGCUAUUUUUAUAAUUAACUUUGGGACUGGAGUCCUCCCAAUGCUUAAUGACCUUGAAUUACAGUAGGAAGGUUGCAAAAGAUUCAAUGCUAUUAAAAAUAAACCACAUUCAGUUUUUAAAAUAUGAUAUAUGUAGAAUACCAUGCUAGAAAUAACAAAUUAUGCUUUGACCUGAAUGUUUCAAAACUUUCCUAGGAGCUCAUACUCAUACACGUCAACACUACCCAUGACCGGAAAAAUGACAACUGGCCUACCGAACUGGUCCUUCUGGCUUUUCACACUGCAGUGCUUGUUUGAAAUACAGUUGACCCUUGAACACAACACAUUUGAACUUGGAGGGUCCACUUAUAUGGAUUUUUUCAAUACAGUCAGCCCUCCAUACAUUCUGGGUCCUGCAACCGAAACCAAAUGCGAAUGGAAAAUACAAUACUCAGAAUGCGAUAAGUUGCGGCAUGAUGGCUACCGCAGUUCUCAGUACUACUCUCAGGGACCCACCUUUGCGGCCAACGCCAGCCCAUUCUGUGAUGAUUACCAAGAUGAAGAUGAAGAAACAGAUCAAAAGUGUUCUCUGUCUUCAUCAGAAGAAGAAAGAUUUAUUUCCAUCAGGAGACCUAAAACACCAGCCUCAAGUGACUUCUCCGACCUUAAUACUCAGACGAACUGGACCAAGUCGCUUCCACUGCCAACACCAGAAGAGAAGAUGCGACAGCAAGCCCAAACAGUCCAGGCUGACGUGGUGCCUAUUAACAUAACUGGGGAGAAUUUCGAUCGCCAGGCCAGCCUUCGGCGGUCUCUAAUUUACACAGACACUCUGGUAAGACGACCGAAGAAAGUCAAAAGGAGAAAGACUAUUACAGGAGUCCCUGACAACAUACAGAAGGAGCUAGCAUCAGGCACUGGCCAAGAUGAUGCUGAUGGCCACUCAGUGUACACCCCUGAUCACUACUCUACACUAGGAAGGUUCAAUAGCUGUCGGUCUGCUGGGCAGCGCUCAGAAACCAGGGACUCCAGCUGUCAGACGGAGGAUGUGAAGGUCGUACCACCUUCCAUGAGGAGAAUCAGGGCACAGAAGGGGCAAGGCAUUGCUGCCCAGAUGGGCCACUUCUCAGGUUCCUCUGGCAACAUGUCUGUGCUGAGCGAUUCUGCAGGGAUCGUAUUCCCUUCCCGCCUUGACAGUGAUGCUGGCUUCCAUAGUCUUCCGCGUUCUGGAGCAAGGGCAAACAUUCAGUCCCUUGAGCCGAGGCUGGGUGCCCUCGGCCCUGCAGGAGACAUGAAUGGCACUUUCCUCUACCAGAGAGGUCACCCACAAGCAGAUGAAAACUUAGGCCAUUUAGGAGGUGCCUCAGGGACUGGAACACUUUUGAGACCCAAAUCCCAGGAGUUGAGACACUUCGAGAGUGAAAAUAUAAUGAGCCCAGCGUGUGUGGUUUCUCCUCAUGCAACCUACUCCACCAGCAUCAUCCCAAAUGCCACACUGUCUUCCUCUUCCGAGGUCAUCGCUAUUCCCACUGCUCAGAGUGCGGGACAGCGGGAAAGUAAAAGUUCUGGCUCAUCACAUGCAAGGAUAAAAUCCAGAGACCACCUCAUCUCCAGGCAUGCUGUGAAAGGUGAUCCUCAGUCUCCCGGUCGCCACUGGAAUGAGGGCCAUGCCACCAUUCUUUCACAGGACUUAGACCCUCAUUCCCCUGGUGAACCCGCACUGUUGUCCCUCUGUGACUCAGCCGUCCCUCUAAAUGCUCCAGCAAAUAGGGAGAAUGGGUCCCAAGCUAUGCCGUAUAAUUGUAGAAACAACCUGGCCUUCCCAGCCCACCCCCAAGAUGUGGAUGGCAAGAGUGAAUCUAGUUAUUCAGGGGGCGGAGGGCACAGCAGCUCGGAGCCCUGGGAAUACAAAUCCUCAGGUAAUGGAAGGGCAUCCCCCCUGAAGCCGCAUUUAGCAACUCCUGGCUAUUCCACUCCCACAAGUAACAUGAGCAGCUGCAGUUUGGACCAAACGUCCAACAAAGAGGAUGCUGGGUCGCUGUAUUCUGAGGACCACGAUGGCUACUGUGCAUCUGUGCACACUGACUCUGGACAUGGAUCUGGGAAUCUGUGCAAUAGCAGUGAUGGCUUUGGGAACCCCAGGCACAGCGUGAUCAAUGUUUUUGUUGGAAGAGCUCAGAAAAACCAAGGGGACCGGUCCAAUUACCAGGAUAAAUCCCUAUCAAGAAACAUCUCUUUGAAGAAAGCAAAGAAGCCUCCCCUGCCACCCUCCCGGACAGACUCCCUCCGCAGGAUUCCCAAGAAGAGCAGCCAGUGCAACGGGCAGGUGCUCAACGAGAGCCUGAUCGCCACACUCCAGCACUCGCUGCAGCUGAGCCUCCCAGGCAAGAGUGGCAGCUCGCCCUCCCAGAGCCCCUGCAGUGACUUGGAAGAGCCCUGGCUGCCCCGCUCCCGGAGCCAGAGCACAGUUAGUGCUGGCAGCAGCAUGACUUCCGCCACCACCCCCAAUGUCUACUCCCUGUGCGGGGCCACGCCAUCGCAGAGUGACACAAGCAGCGUCAAGUCAGAGUACACGGACCCCUGGGGUUAUUACAUUGACUACACGGGCAUGCAGGAAGAUCCGGGGAACCCGGCAGGGGGCUGUUCAACCAGCAGUGGGGUGCCCACUGGGAACGGGCCAGUCCGCCAUGUCCAAGAAGGGUCCAGAGCCACAAUGCCCCAAGUGCCCGGUGGUUCAGUCAAACCAAAGAUCAUGUCACCAGAGAAGUCACACAGAGUCAUUUCUCCAUCCAGUGGGUAUUCCAGCCAGUCGAAUACACCCACAGCACUCACCCCUGUGCCUGUGUUUUUAAAAUCAGUGUCACCAGCAAACGGGAAGGGGAAGCCCAAGCCCAAGGUACCAGAAAGGAAGUCCUCUCUGAUAUCUUCAGUAUCCAUUUCCUCAUCGUCCACUUCUCUUUCUUCUAGUACUUCUACUGAAGGAAGUGGCACUAUGAAGAAGCUGGAUCCAGCCGUGGGCUCUCCCCCGGCUCCUCCUCCUCCUCCUGUUCCCUCUCCUCCAUUCCCUUGUCCUGCAGACAGGUCUCCUUUCCUUCCUCCCCCACCUCCUGUCACAGAUUGCUCCCAGGGCUCUCCUCUGCCUCACUCUCCUGUGUUCCCCCCUCCGCCGCCAGAAGCUCUCAUUCCUUUCUGCUCCCCACCUGAUUGGUGCCUUUCUCCUCCCCGCCCUGCACUGAGCCCCAUUCUUCCAGAUUCACCUGUGUCCUUGCCAUUGCCCCCACCUCUCUUACCUUCCUCGGAACCCCCACCUGCCCCACCUCUUGACCCCAAAUUCAUGAAAGACACCAGGCCGCCUUUCACAAAUUCUGGCCAGCCAGAAUCCUCCCGGGGAUCCUUGAGGCCGCCUUCUACCAAGGAGGAGACCAGCAGGCCCCCCAUGCCCCUGAUAACCACGGAAGCAUUGCAGAUGGUGCAGUUGAGGCCCGUGAGAAAGAACUCAGGCGCUGAGGCGGCACAGUUGUCUGAACGAACAGCUCAGGAACAACGAACUCCAGUUGCUCCACAGUACCACUUAAAGCCAUCUGCUUUCCUGAAAUCCCGAAAUAGCACAAAUGAAAUGGAGAGUGAAAGCCAGCCUGCCUCUGUGACAAGCUCGCUUCCGACGCCUGCCAAGAGCUCGAGUCAGGGUGACCAUGGCAGUGCGGCUGAGCGUGGUGGCCCUGUGAGCCGCAGCCCUGGAGCUCCAAGCGCUGGGGAGGCAGAGGCUCGGCCCAGCCCCAGCACCACCCCACUCCCAGACUCUUCACCCAGCAGGAAGCCACCCCCCAUUUCCAAGAAGCCCAAACUGUUCCUGGUGGUACCACCUCCGCAGAAAGAUUUUGCAGUGGAGCCCGCAGAGAACGUGAGCGAAGCCCUCCGAGCUGUGCCCAGCCCCACGACGGGAGAGGAGGGCUCUGUGCACAGCAGGGAGGCAAAAGAGAGUUCUGCAGCCCAAGCUGGCUCUCAUGCCACGCACCCUGGCACCUCGGUUCUUGAGGGAGGAGCUGCAGGAUCCAUGUCUCCCAGCAGAGUGGAAGCCAAUGUCCCCAUGGUUCAGCCUGAUGUCUCACCAGCCCCCAAGCAGGAGGAGCCAGCCGAGAACAGUGCGGAUACUGGGGGCGAUGGGGAGAGCUGCCUAUCUCAACAGGACGGAGCAGCUGGGGUGCCGGAGACCAACGCAGCCGGUUCAUCCUCAGAGGCCUGUGACUUCCUCAAGGAAGACGGGAAUGAUGAGGUAAUGACCCCCAGUCGACCCAGGACCACAGAAGACCUUUUUGCAGCUAUUCACAGAUCCAAAAGGAAAGUCCUCGGCCGUAGAGAUUCAGAUGAUGACCACUCCCGAAACCAUUCUCCCUCCCCGCCCGUGACACCCACCGGCGCUGCCCCAAGCCUGGCCUCUCCAAAGCAAGUGGGGUCGAUUCAGAGAAGCAUCCGAAAGAGCAGCACCAGCAGUGACAACUUCAAAGCUCUGCUGCUGAAAAAGGGCAGUCGUUCAGACACCAGCGCCCGCAUGUCUGCAGCAGAGAUGCUCAAGAACACAGACCCUAGAUUCCAGAGGUCGAGGUCAGAGCCUUCCCCAGAUGCCCCCGAGAGCCCGUCAAGCUGCUCCCCAAGCAAGAACAGAAGGGCGCAGGAGGAGUGGGCCAAGAACGAAGGCUUGAUGCCUCGGAGUCUGUCCUUUUCCGGCCCCAGGUACGGCCGCAGCCGAACGCCGCCUUCUGCCGCCAGCAGCAGGUACAGCAUGCGGAACCGGAUCCAGAGCAGCCCCAUGACCGUCAUCUCGGAGGGAGAAGGGGAAGCCGUGGAGCCUGUGGACAGCAUAGCCCGCGGGGCUCUGGGCGCUGCGGAGGGAUGUUCCCUGGACGGACUGGCGAGGGAGGAGAUGGACGAGGGCGGCCUGCUCUGUGGGGAGGGGCCUGCCGCCUCCCUGCAGCCCCAGGCCCCCGGCCCUGUGGAUGGGACAGCCAGUGCAGAGGGCAGAGAGCCCUCCCCACAGUGUGGCGGUUCUCUGAGCGAGGAGAGUUAGGGCCAAGAACGUAACUCUCCCAGGUGACACGGGGGGAGACGAGCAAUGCAGCACUCUAGGAAGCCUGCUAGGCGCCCUUCCCUGGCUCACCCGGGGAGCCCACUCUGCUUCUGUGCUGUGGGCCCCGGGGUUGCCAGCCCUGCAGUGUGAGUGAACGGUUAUUUAGGACUCACCUGGCACUUGCCCUGUGGCUUAAGAACAAGUAGAAGCUUAAACUUCUGAAAGUGCUUCCCGGGGAAGAUUUUUUUUUUUUUUUUUUUUUUUUGCUAAAUGCUGGGUGUGUAUGUGUGCAUUUUCCACACUUUUUAAUUUUUAAAAAAUACACAUAUACACAAACAACAUGUACAGAAAUAGAAGAAAGCAAGCCAGACUUAAGCUUGGUAGAGUAACGGAGUCCUCUGGUCUAGGCGGUAAUUGCUUUCAGAGAAUUACGUUUAUAGAAAUCAGCGAGUUUUGUAAGAAAGGAGAAGAUGUUACUUCAAGAAAGAGGCAGUAGAGUUGCUGGUUCUUAAUGCACAGAACACACAGAUAUAUGCACACGUGUGCUGCUGAGGUGAGGCAGGUCUGGUGAGCACGGAGAGGCUGGGAAGGGGCUAAGUGACUAAUUGGUUCAGGUACUUUUUUCUGGGGGAGGUAGACUUUGCUUCUUUUUUGUAAAAAUGACAAACGUAGAAGUGGCAAUGCUGUAACCUGGUGCCUGCUGCUGUGCAGCCACAUACACACAAUUGUAGCCUGAUUUUUAGAAGUGUGGGUAAUUUUUUAAUGAAUUUCCUCCUUGAGUAGCAGCUGAGGUCAUUGACAACUGAAGUGAUGGUGUGGACAUAGAGAGAGGGGAAGGGUUGGAAAGGAGUAAGUGAUACACUGCUGGAAUUUGUUUCCUGCCUAUGAAAUAAAAUUAUUUUUCAGAAUUAAAUUUGAAAACUUGCACUACAGAACUAUGGGUGGAGCUUUUCCUUUUACAACAGUUUUUUUUUUUUUUUUUUUUUAACCAGAGUUUAAACUUCCAUUAGGCAAUUUCCUGUCACUUGAAAUGUCAACAUUUGCUAACUUUUGGAUAUCCUUUUGGUUACACCAAAGAAAAAGUUAUGGCUAUUUUUUUUUCCUUGAACUGCCUACAGUAUCAUGUCCUAAUUCAGAAAGAUUUAUCAAAAUCUAUUAUAUAUUAUCUUACUUUGAAGAAAAUGCUGAAUAGCUCUUGUUAGUCAAAUAAACUGAUAAAAAUUGGUAGGGCCUGGCUAUCAAUUAGCCCUGGGAAAUGAAUUUUUAGAUUAAAAAGGUUUUUUUGCAUCAUUUGGUUUGUGCAUUUUUAUAUUUGUUUAUAAAUAAUUGAGUUGCUAAUUACUUCUAAUCUUCUCCAAUCAGAUUUUCAACAAUUUUAGACAUGGGACACACGUGUGUGAAGUCUUUAUUUUAAUGUAAUAAUCUCAUUACCCCCACCCUUACUCCCUUAACUUCCAUGUACUUAGACUCCUUUAUUUGUUAAAUAAACUAGAGUAUUGUCUUCUUCAUUAGAAGGACCUAGGAUGACAAUGCGGAGAGUCUUGGUCUGAAUCUAGUGCGACUACCACCUGCCAGCUUUUGGGGGGUAUGGAAAUACUAUCUAAAAGUUGGACUGCAUGGGUCAAAUCAUUAUGAGACUUAUAAACUAAAACUUUAGAUACCCAUAUAGAAAUGUCUUUGAGGCAAAAACAAACCUAAAGAAUGAAGGCUCUUUCCCUUCUCUGAAAAAAACAAAACACUGCUCUUCACACAACCGGAAGUCAAGACCAGAGAUUUGGAGCAAUUGUCUACUAAUUUGGCACAAAGAUCGUUUCUUUAGAAAAGUGGCAUUGGCUUUUGAAUAUGAAAUCUUCUCAUAGCUGCCUAAAAAAGACUAGAAUGUAUAUGGAUAUCAGAAACCUUUAAUAAUACAUAAUUUAUGCAAAGAUAAGAUAAAGCAACAUAACACUAAUUAUAAAACUAUUUUUAAAUCCCCAUUUUUAAUGAAAAAUAUACAUUUGUAUUUAAUUUCCUUUGAAUAAAACAAUUGUAAAGUAAA